AGGAGUGAGGCGAGCGGGGCGCGCGGAGCGGACGCCGCGGAUCUUGUGCUGCGCCACCGCGCCCACUCGGCAGCUCGGGAGGCGGGGACCGGCCCGGAGGCUGCGCCGCUGCGGGGCCGGCCGACUCGGAGGAGGAGAGGGAGGAGGCGCCGCCGGCCCGGGCUGGAGCCGAGCGCAGCAGCCACCGCCGCCGCCGCGCCAGAAGUUUGGGUUGAACCGGAGCUGCCGGGAGGAAACUUUUUUCUUUUUUCCCCCUCCCUCCCGGGAGGAGGAGGAGGAGGAGGAGGGGAAGCUGCCGCCGGCGCCAAGGCUCGUGGGCUCGGGGUCGGCGCGGCCCGCAGAAGGGGCGGGGGCCUCGCCCCGCGAGGGGAGGCGCGCCCCGGGGGCCCCGAGAGGGGCGGUGAGGACCGCGGGCUGCUGGUGCGGCGGCGGCGGCGCGUGUGCCCCGCGCAGGGGAGGGCGCCCGCCCCGCUCCCGGCCCGGCUGCGAGGAGGAGGCGGCGGCGGCGCAGGAGGAUGUACUUGGUGGCGGGGGACAGGGGGUUGGCCGGCUGCGGGCACCUCCUGGUCUCGCUGCUGGGGCUGCUGCUGCUGCUGGCGCGCUCCGGCACCCGGGCGCUGGUCUGCCUGCCCUGUGACGAGUCCAAGUGCGAGGAGCCCAGGAACUGCCCGGGGAGCAUCGUGCAGGGCGUCUGCGGCUGCUGCUACACGUGCGCCAGCCAGAGGAACGAGAGCUGCGGCGGCACCUUCGGGAUUUACGGAACCUGCGACCGGGGGCUGCGUUGUGUCAUCCGCCCCCCGCUCAAUGGCGACUCCCUCACCGAGUACGAAGCGGGCGUUUGCGAAG